AGAGCUGCUGCCGCCUGCGCCCAGGGCUGCACUCCGCGCAGGCCUCAUAGCCAGGCCAUGGCCCCCACAGAGCCCUGGAGCCCCAGCCCGGGGUCAGCGCCCUGGGACUACUCGGGGUUGGACGGCCUGGAGGAGCUGGAGCUGUGUCCGGCCGGGGACCUGCCCUACGGCUACGUCUACAUCCCCGCGCUCUACCUGGCGGCCUUCGCCGUGGGCCUGCUGGGCAACGCCUUUGUGGUGUGGCUGCUGGCCGGGCGGCGGGGCCCGCGGCGGCUGGUGGAUACCUUCGUGCUGCACCUGGCGGCAGCUGACCUGGGCUUCGUGCUCACGCUGCCGCUGUGGGCCGCGGCGGCGGCGCUAGGCGGCCGCUGGCCGUUCGGCGAUGGCCUCUGCAAGCUCAGCAGCUUCGCGCUGGCGGGCACGCGCUGCGCGGGCGCGCUGCUGCUGGCGGGCAUGAGCGUGGACCGCUACCUGGCCGUGGUGAAGCUGCUCGAGGCGAGGCCACUGCGCACCCCGCGCUGCGCGCUGGCCUCGUGCUGCGGCGUCUGGGCCGUGGCGCUGCUGGCCGGCCUGCCCUCCCUGGUCUACCGGGGGUUGCAGCCCCUGCCUGGGGGCCAGGACAGCCAGUGCGGCGAGGAGCCCUCCCACGCCUUCCAGGGCCUCAGCUUGCUGCUGCUGCUGCUGACCUUCGUGCUGCCCCUGGUCGUCACCCUCUUCUGCUACUGCCGCAUCUCGCGCCGCCUGCGACGGCCGCCGCACGUGGGUCGGGCCCGGAGGAACUCGCUGCGCAUCAUCUUCGCCAUCGAGAGCACGUUUGUGGGCUCCUGGCUGCCCUUCAGCGCCCUGCGGGCCGUCUUCCACCUGGCGCGUCUGGGGGCGCUGCCGCUGCCGUGCCCCCUGCUGCUGGCGCUGCGCUGGGGCCUCACCAUUGCCACCUGCCUGGCCUUCGUCAACAGCUGCGCCAACCCGCUCAUCUACCUCCUGCUGGACCGCUCAUUCCGAGCCCGGGCGCUGGACGGGGCCUGCGGGCGCACCGGCCGCCUGGCGCGAAGGAUCAGCUCAGCCUCCUCGCUCUCCAGGGACGACAGUUCCGUGUUCCGUUGCCGGGCCCAGGCCGCGAACACUGCCUCGGCCUCCUGGUAGCUGCCCCGGGCCGCUGGAGGUGGGCGGCAGCGGAGCAUCGAGAGGAGGCCAGAGG